CAAAUUUAUAAAUUUAACUUUAUCAUAGGUCUGCAUGUAUAGAAAAAAAGCACUGUAUAUAUAGAGUUCAGUAUUAUCGACUGUUUCAAGCAUCUACUGGGGGUCUUGGAACAUAGCCCCAUGAAUAAGGAAUAACUACUAUAUAUUGUAAAGUUAAAGUAUAAACCUAAUAUCUAGAGUUCAUUUAUUUAUUCAACAAAUAUACCUUUGGCACUGAUGGCCUGCUAGACUUUCAGCCCAAUACUGGUGUAAAAUGAUAAAUAAGACAGUCAUGGAAUCUACUCGGAUUUCACAGUCUAAUCAGAGACACAAAUAAUUGAUAUAGUAACAAUUGUGACAAGUGCUAUGAAAAAAAAAGGAAUGGGUGCUGUAAAAUUUGUAAUGGGAAAGAGGACCAUCUCUUCACAGAGGAUACAGAAGCUGCUUCCUUCUGCAUCUCCCACUGUUGGCUAGAAUACAUUUCUGUUUAUUAGGAUUGUCAUUUGGAAAGGCUGCAUAUUGAAUCUGUAUGGCUCAGGGUCAGACAGGGACAUUUCAAUUGCAGCUGAGAGUAUGGCAGUUGCAGAACAACCACAGAUCAGGAAGAUGAGAAGAGUAGCAUGAUGACCCUAAAGAAAUACCAAACCCAGGAGGCAGAAGAAAGAGCCAUCUAGUCCUAGCGUGGAGCAUAUUGUACUUCUCCAUUUUCUAAUCCCAGAGCACCAUGUGGCCUUAGGGGAAUAUAUGGAUGAAAAGAAAAAGCUGGUGUGCUGCCGAUGUCAGACCCUGCCACUAGCCUCCUUAACAGAAGUUCCCAGCCAUGAAGCCUCUCCUUGUUGUGUUUGUCUUUCUUUUCCUUUGGGAUCCAGUGCUGGCAGGUAUAAAUUCAUUAUCAUCAGAAAUGCACAAGAAAUGCUAUAAAAAUGGCAUCUGCAGACUUGAAUGCUAUGAGAGUGAAAUGUUAGUUGCCUACUGUAUGUUUCAGCUGGAGUGCUGUGUCAAAGGAAAUCCUGCACCCUGACAUAAGAAACCAAUGAAUGGCCACUAUCCUGUAGGCCCUUGAUUCUGCCAUCUUUCACAAAACCAGGGAAUUUAGAUCAAACUGUGACACCAUGAUGUGUCCAUGACUACUGGUUUUUAGCAUUUUUAUAGGCCAGCAGACUCUUGUGGUCUUAAAUUUAAAGAGCUGAGCUGUAGCCUUCUUUAAAAGAGCUCGGUUUUUCACAAAAACAAUGUAGAAGAUAUUUUCUCACCUCAACGUGAUGUCCAGUGUGCUCAUCAGCACCUGUUUCUCCCUCUAAUCAUAGAGGAUAUUCUUAUUAUUUAGAAAGGCUUCAAGGGAAACAACUUUUGACACCUAAGUCGUGUCCUACCUUCGCUUCAGCUUCGCAUUUCCCAUUUCUGUGAAAUUCCCAACUUUAGAGAAGCAGAUUUGCCAUGGCCUUCUGACAACCUUGUACAUCUCUCACAUAAACCGCAUAGGCAGGGCUUAACUACAGGCUGGCCCGAGUCUGCACUGAGUCUGACCCUGAAGUUCCUUUGGAACAGGAGAGGCCAUCUUGUGAUGGGCUGGAACAAGGUAAUUUCUCAUCCACCUCCCUAGUUUCAGUUGAGCAAUGGAACUUCCCACCUGAGCCCCUAGGGUUCAGCUACAGGCUAUAAGACUGCCGUCCUGUGGUUUAGUGUUGGUUCCUUAGCAGCAGAGUGAUGCCACCUCUGCUGCCCGUCAUCUGACUCCUCUGGAUGGGUGUUAUCCUGUGGCUUAAGAGCUAACACCAUGCUGAUCUUGCUUUGCUAUAUGUGUAACUAAUAAACUGCCUAAAUGCA